ACACACACAUCUGCACCUCAACCACAGACUACACUUGCUGAACUGGCUCCUGGGGCCAUGAGGCUGUCACUGCCACUGCUGCUGCUGCUGCUGGGAGCCUGGGCCAUCCCAGGGGGCCUCGGGGACAGGGCGCCACUCACAGCCACAGCCCCACAACUGGAUGAUGAGGAGAUGUACUCAGCCCACAUGCCCGCUCACCUGCGCUGUGAUGCCUGCAGAGCUGUGGCUUACCAGGCCCAUCCUUGAGUCCGGACUCCCUCCCCAACCCUGACGGGGCGGCUUUGGCUAUGUGUACAUGGUGCAAGUGCACACGUGUGAGCGCCUGCACAGACUCUGCUCCUAUCCUCCCCACCUCCCCCUAACUGAGCAGCAGUCCUGAGGCCCUGCCUCCCAGUCCCUCCUUGUUCCAGAUGUGGCAAAAUCUGGCAAAGGCAGAGACCAAACUUCAUACCUCAAACUCUGGGGGGCGGCGGGAGCUGAGCGAGUUGGUCUACACGGAUGUCCUGGACCGGAGCUGCUCCCGGAACUGGCAGGACUACGGAGUUCGAGAAGUGGACCAAGUGAAACGUCUCACAGGCCCAGGACUUAGCGAGGGGCCAGAGCCAAGCAUCAGCGUGAUGGUCACAGGGGGCCCCUGGCCUACCAGGCUCUCCAGGACAUGUUUGCACUACUUGGGGGAGUUUGGAGAAGACCAGAUCUAUGAAGCCCACCAACAAGGCCGAGGGGCUCUGGAGGCAUUGCUAUGUGGGGGACCCCAGGGGGCCUGCUCAGAGAAGGUGUCAGCCACAAGAGAAGAGCUCUAGUCCUGGACUCUACCCUCCUCUGAAAGAAGCUGGGGCUUGCUCUGACGGUCUCCACUCCCGUCUGCAGGCAGCCAGGAGGGCAGGAAGCCCUUGCUCUGUGCUGCCAUCCUGCCUCCCUCCUCCAGCCUCAGGGCACUCGGGCCUGGGUGGGAGUCAACGCCUUCCCCUCUGGACUCAAAUAAAACCCAGUGACCUCACUUCUUUUCUCUGCAAAAGGUGCUUGUGGGGCUGGGAGUGCAGACAUUGGUGUUUCUGCUGAUGUCCCUUGUGAAAAAAAAAAAAAAACUCUCAAAAUCAA